AGUAGCAGCAGCGCCGGGUCCCGUGCGGAGGUGCUCCUCGCAGAGUUGUUUCUCGAGCAGCGGCAGUUCUCACUACAGCGCCAGGACGAGUCCGGUUCGUGUUCGUCCGCGGAGAUCUCUCUCAUCUCGCUCGGCUGCGGGAAAUCGGGCUGAAGCGACUGAGUCCGCGAUGGAGAAAACUUUAGAAACUGUUCCUUUGGAGAGGAAAAAGAGAGAAAAGGAACAGUUCCGUAAGCUCUUUAUUGGUGGCUUAAGCUUUGAAACCACAGAAGAAAGUUUGAGGAACUACUACGAACAAUGGGGAAAGCUUACAGACUGUGUGGUAAUGAGGGAUCCUGCAAGCAAAAGAUCAAGAGGAUUUGGUUUUGUAACUUUUUCAUCCAUGGCUGAGGUUGAUGCUGCCAUGGCUGCAAGACCUCAUUCAAUUGAUGGGAGAGUAGUUGAGCCAAAACGUGCUGUAGCAAGAGAGGAAUCUGGAAAACCAGGGGCUCAUGUAACUGUGAAGAAGCUGUUUGUUGGCGGAAUUAAAGAAGAUACUGAGGAACAUCACCUUAGAGAUUACUUUGAGGAAUAUGGAAAAAUUGAUACCAUUGAGAUAAUUACUGAUAGGCAGUCUGGAAAGAAAAGAGGCUUUGGCUUUGUUACUUUUGAUGACCAUGAUCCUGUGGAUAAAAUCGUAUUGCAGAAAUACCAUACCAUCAAUGGUCAUAAUGCAGAAGUAAGAAAGGCUUUGUCUAGACAAGAAAUGCAGGAAGUUCAGAGUUCUAGGAGUGGAAGAGGAGGCAACUUUGGCUUUGGGGAUUCACGUGGUGGCGGUGGAAAUUUCGGACCAGGACCAGGAAGUAACUUUAGAGGAGGAUCUGAUGGAUAUGGCAGUGGACGUGGAUUUGGGGAUGGCUAUAAUGGGUAUGGAGGAGGACCUGGAGGUGGCAAUUUUGGAGGUAGCCCCGGUUAUGGAGGAGGAAGAGGAGGAUAUGGUGGUGGAGGACCUGGAUAUGGCAACCAGGGUGGGGGCUACGGAGGUGGUUAUGACAACUAUGGAGGAGGAAAUUAUGGAAGUGGAAAUUACAAUGAUUUUGGAAAUUAUAACCAGCAACCUUCUAACUACGGUCCAAUGAAGAGUGGAAACUUUGGUGGUAGCAGGAACAUGGGGGGACCAUAUGGUGGAGGAAACUAUGGUCCAGGAGGCAGUGGAGGAAGUGGGGGUUAUGGUGGGAGGAGCCGAUACUGAGCUUCUUCCUAUUUGCCAUGGGCUUCACUGUAUAAAUAGGAGAGGAUGAGAGCCCAGAGGUAACAGAACAGCUUCAGGUUAUCGAAAUAACAAUGUUAAGGAAACUCUUAUCUCAGUCAUGCAUAAAUAUGCAGUGAUAUGGCAGAAGACACCAGAGCAGAUGCAGAGAGCCAUUUUGUGAAUGGAUUGGAUUAUUUAAUAACAUUACCUUACUGUGGAGGAAGGAUUGUAAAAAAAAAUGCCUUUGAGACAGUUUCUUAGCUUUUUAAUUGUUGUUUCUUUCUAGUGGUCUUUGUAAGAGUGUAGAAGCAUUCCUUCUUUGAUAAUGUUAAAUUUGUAAGUUUCAGGUGACAUGUGAAACCUUUUUUAAGAUUUUUCUCAAAGUUUUGAAAAGCUAUUAGCCAGGAUCAUGGUGUAAUAAGACAUAACGUUUUUCCUUUAAAAAAAUUUAAGUGCGUGUGUAGAGUUAAGAAGCUGUUGUACAUUUAUGAUUUAAUAAAAUAAUUCUAAAGGAAAUUGUGUAAUUAUAGACUUUUUAUUUUAAAUAAGUUAAGGAGUGGGUAGUAUAAUUAAGGUCCGUUGCAAAGCUGUUGUUAUAUUUGUAUAAGAUAAAUGCUGGUCAGAUGUAAGUGUGUUGUCUGCAAUUCAUCAGGAUUAAAUUAUGUAGAUAACUUAAGGGAUAUCUCUGCAAGGAGAAACACCUUUUUAGAUCUUUUAGAUGCUGCUUCUUCAAUGCAAGGAAAGGAAAUAACCCCAGCGAGGUACUCUUCAGGGACACAGGUCUAGUACAAGAGAACUCUUGACGGCUACUAAGUUCAGCCAGUCUUAAAAAACUGUGCUGUUUCUACAAAACUUUAACUACAGUAGUUUAUAAGGAUGCCAACGAAAGCUGAGGGUGUAGAGCAAAAUAGUUCUAAGCUUCAGUUAAACUUCUUUAGGUAAGAUCUUAUUUACUUUUCCUUUCUUAAUUUUCCUCCCUAAAAGAUAAACUAAUACUCUUAAAUGGUCUUUCAGUAUAGUGGUUCUUACGUAGUUUAACAUAGCUAUAAAUUGAGUUUAACAAUUUAUAAACUCAAGAGAAUAAUUUUUAUAAACCCUGUUUUCCAAUCUGUCAUUUACUUAAAUUAUUUUGGUUGUUUUUCCCUUUUUUUCCUUCUUUUCCCACCCCCUCCCCCUCCAUGUGAAGAUUUGGGUGCUUAACAUAUCAUUUUUUUCCCUGCCGGAAUUUUAGCAUUGAUAUGAACCAUGGACAAGUAUAUUCUGCUGCCACAAAGACUGUAAAGUGCUUCAUUUCAACAGCUGAGGCAAGCCAAGUGAUCAUUAAUAAAGCUUUUCUUGGUUCCUUCAGUGGUGUUGGUAGUAAAAUGGUAGGUAAAAGUUAGGCUGCAAGUUCAAUAAAUCAUGAGAUUUCCCAUCGUUACACCCUUGUGUAUUCACAUUUCUUGGAUCAAACAUUUUGAGUGAACUAGGGGUUUUUAUUAAAGACAUUUGUUGUAUUUAUGGUUGUAACUGUACAUGCUUAUCAGGAUGAGACUGAAAGAAGGUAGGGCAAAAAUGGUUGAAUCUAUUUUCAGAUAGUAGUUCAUACUUGAGUGAAGUGUCUUGUCUGCAUUAUGAAGCCUGGUAUGUAUCCAGUACUAAAUAGGUGGGUUAAAUGUGGUAAUUCUAGUUCAGUGUCUUACCCUGAAGAGAAAGUUGUAGGUUGGCUGUUGAAAUUCAUUCCUUAGAUAUGAUCAGUUUGAUUGCCCGGCUUUAUUGCCUUUACAGGAAUGUGAUACUCAGGGCUUACUCUAUACACCAAUGAGUCUUCUUUGAUCCUAAGACCACCACUGAAGUUGUUUAGGUUCUUUUGGACAAACAUGAUAAACUUCUUCAGAUACUUUUUUUUUCCUUUGGCAGGAAGGUGUCUUGCUGCAGGUAACUAAUGAAGAAGUGGUCAACCACAGAGUCUUCAAGAAAUAAGAAAUUCUGUACCAUCUGAAAGUAGUUCUUGUUGGUGCCUUCAUUUAAAAAGCACUCUUUAAAAUAAAAGGGAAAUGUUUUCUGAUAAAACAAACAUUUAGUUGAGGUUCUUGAUAUAAAACAAUUACAAAAUGAGUGUUGUUUGUAAAACAGUAACAUCAAAUUGGCUAGAGAGAUAAAUGUAUCAUGUUUUAAAUUAGGUUUUGUGAGUAGACAGAUUACAAUUCUAUUUUAAAUAUAAAGUUUAUAAAAUAAAUACUUUUUGUAUCCAAAUACUUGGUGUAAUGUUUACACAUAAAAUGUGUGAAUCUUGUUCUAUAAAUAUUUGGUUGUCUAAAAGAUCACCAUCCCCUAAAUUUUUAAAAGCAGUUUCACAAAGCUAUGCAUAUUUUAAUAUUAACAGGUAAAUGAGAAGAGCAUUGUGGACAUUAUUGGCUGUCCCCAAUAAAAUGCUGUUCAUUAUGCACUGUA